AUGUCGUUCAUCUCCAGCAACUUCUCCUUCGAAGCUGCCCUCCAGGCCUUGCAUGUGCCCUGCCUGUUCCCCGGGCCUCCCUGCCUGCCCCAAAGGCCUCUGACUCCUCUGGACACCCAAGUUGCCUGGGUCCUUCAUCAUAACCAUCCUUUAUCGGGUUGUGUGAAGAGCCUGGCCCAGUUGCCUCGCUGGGCCUCCCACCCAGCCCCUGUGAUACAGGUGUUACUGUCCCUUCACAGAAGAAGAGCUCGAGCGGGGAGGUACGGACCGUCUCCUCUCGCACGGGCAGGACGACACCCUCCCUCCCCCCCUUUUUUCUGCCAACGUCUAUCUCAACGCGCGCGCACAUACGGAGAUUGUGCGGCUUUUUUCCCCCUUGGGAGAAAAAACGGGGAGAGUAAAAGAAGAGAGACCAAAGAGAAGAACUCCUCCUCGGCGAGCUCCGCACUCCGUGCCGCGGCCCGGCGCGGGGACGCCGCCGCCGCCCGCCCGCUCUCUCCCGGCCCUGCGGCGGGUGCCAGUACGAGCGCGAGCGAGGGCACUGCACCCGGGGACGCUGCGAGACUUUUCGGCGCUCGAGCCGACCUCGCCGCCGCCGCGGCAGGCAGAAGAGACAGGAGCGAGAAGGGCCCUGCCUCCCCCUCGCCUUCCUCGCCCGGCGCCCCGCGCCCGGCCGGGCCGCGCAGGCAGGCGGAGGGAAGGAGGGAGGCUGCGAGGAGGCGGGCGGAGCAGAGGCCCCGGCGAAGCGCGCUGCGGCCGCCCGCCCGUGGAUGCGGCGCCCAGGGAUCCUGGAGACAACUUUGCCGUGUGACGCGCCGGGAGGACUGCAGGGCCCGCGGCCGAGGGCUCGGCGCCGCCUGUGAGCGGGCCCGCGCGGCCGGCUCUCCCGGGCACCAAGCUUGCUCCGCGCCACUGCCCGCCGGCCCGCGGCGAGGACGACCUGCCCGUCUCCGCCGCCGGCGGCCCUUCCUGGCGCGAGGCAGUGAGGGCGAGGCGCUCAGGUGCGAGCGCGGGGCCCCGCCGCAGCGCCCGCCGCAGCGCCGCGCCAAGCCGCGCCCGGCUCCGCUCCGGGGGGCUCCAGCGCCUUCGCUUCCGUCUCAGCCAAGUUGCGUGGACCCGCUCUUUCGCCACCUUCCCCAGCCGCCGGCCGAACCGCCGCUCCCACUGACGCUGCUUUCGCUUCACCCGAACCGGGGCUGCGGGGCCCCCGACGCGGAAAGGAUGGGGAGAAGGCUGCAGAUGCCGAGGCGCCCCGAGACGCCCGUGCGGCAGUGACCCGCGACCUCCGCCCCGCCCGGCGCGCCCCUCGGGCCCCCGGGGCCCUCGGCGCCCCUUCCCUGCCGCGCGGGAACCC